ACAUAGGCGGAAGUGGCCUGCGGGCGCCGGAGUUGAGAGUGCUUUCCGGGGAGGCGACCGCCGCGGUGGAAAGUGCAGGAGUGGGCGAGGAGGAGGAGGAAGAGGAGGUGAUGGCGACGGACCAGGGGAGGGGGAGAUGCUCCGUCUAGCUCAGACGCCACGCAGGCUGCCGUCACCCUUCCGGGUGACAUACCGGCCUUGGGGUACGCGUGCCUUCGGGGCCUUUCCUGUGUUUGGGACCCAGAUCUCCUCUCCUCCAGAAAACCUUGACACUGCCCAUCUUCCUCAUCCAGAAGGAGCGUUCGAGGAAUGGAUGAGGUCGGGAUGGAAGAAACGGGUGAUUCCCUUUUUUGAAAGAGCGGAAACCGGCCGGGCGGUUUCCAGGGAGGAGCAUCUGUUCCUCCUCGCCCGUUUUUCGCCCUCGGGCUGGCGAGAACUCCCUCAGGUCCCAAUCCGUGGACUCGCAGGGGUGAGGUGACCUCAAGGGGUCUUUUACGCUGUUCUCGGGGUCUCUGGAGAACUGUCAGUCACCUGGAUACCUCUAGACUGUAUUUACAGUUAACUGUUUCCUCGUUCCGUGUUUAUUAAAUAGGGGCACUCCAAGGCCAUGAUUGAUUCCGGAGCGCAGUUAAUCAAGGCAUAAUGGCAUGGACUUGACACAGCAAGCAAAAGACAUACAGAACAUAACAGUCCAGGAAACCAACAAAAAUAACUCUGAAAGCAUUGAAUGCAGCAAAAUAACAAUGGAUCUCAAGUUCAACAAUUCCAGGAAAUAUAUUUCUAUCACUGUGCCAUCCAAAACCCAAACAAUGUCACCACACAUCAAGUCAGUUGACGACGUUGUGGUACUUGGCAUGAAUCUCAGCAAGUUUAACAAACUUACUCAGUUUUUCAUAUGUGUUGCUGGAGUUUUUGUAUUUUACCUAAUUUAUGGGUAUUUACAGGAAUUAAUAUUUUCAGUGGAGGGUUUUAAGUCCUGUGGCUGGUACCUUACCUUAGUGCAGUUUGCCUUUUACUCCAUAUUUGGCCUAAUAGAACUUCAGCUUAUUCAGGACAAAAGGAGGAGAAUACCAGGAAAAACCUACAUGAUAAUAGCUUUUCUAACUGUGGGUACUAUGGGGUUAUCAAACACUUCCUUGGGCUACCUGAAUUACCCUACCCAAGUCAUCUUCAAGUGCUGCAAAUUGAUUCCUGUUAUGCUAGGAGGAGUUUUUAUUCAAGGAAAGCGUUAUAAUGUUGCAGAUGUGUCUGCUGCCAUAUGUAUGAGCCUUGGCCUGAUAUGGUUUACCCUCGCUGACAGCACAACUGCACCAAAUUUCAACCUGACGGGUGUGGUGCUUAUUUCCCUGGCACUAUGUGCAGAUGCCGUCAUUGGAAAUGUUCAAGAGAAAGCUAUGAAACUUCAUAAUGCUUCUAAUUCUGAAAUGGUAUUGUAUUCGUAUUCAAUUGGUUUUGUAUACAUUUUACUGGGAUUGACAUGCACUAGUGGAUUAGGCCCUGCAGUAACAUUUUGUGCAAAGAAUCCAGUUCGGACCUAUGGUUAUGCGUUCCUUUUUUCCCUCACUGGAUAUUUUGGAAUCUCCUUUGUUCUGGCUUUGAUUAAAAUUUUUGGUGCACUUAUUGCUGUAACAGUGACAACAGGAAGAAAAGCAAUGACCAUUGUACUUUCGUUUAUAUUCUUUGCUAAACCAUUCACGUUUCAGUAUGUAUGGUCUGGUUUGUUAGUUGUCCUUGGUAUAUUUCUUAAUGUUUACAGCAAAAAUAUGGAUAAAAUAAGACUACCAUCACUGUAUGAUUUGAUAAACAAAUCAGUGGAAGCAAGAAAGUCAAGGACGCUGGCACAGACUGUAUAGACAGUGAUUGUCCUAUUUAAAAUAGAAUUUUAAGGGAACAAUCAUCAAUUAAUUAACUUUCCAAAGGGACUGAUAAAAACCAAAGGAUCUGGAGGCAUUGCUAUCCCAUUUGUGGACAGAUUUCAUAUGAAGUUGUUUUGCGGUGUCAGCCUUUUCUUCAGAGCAUUUGUUUGACUGACUUCCAAAGCAAUCAAGAGAGCCACGUCUAGCAGACUUUACAAUAAAAUGUCAAUAUGAAGGACUGUAAUUCCUAGCAGUUUAUUGAGAAUUUCACUGGAAAUGGACCAUGUGUUGCAAGACUAAUUGGCUAUAAUUAUAUCCUAUCAAAGAAAUCGAUACGUAAUAGCAGAUUGUUUUAUAUUCAUUCCAUUUUGAUGGUGUUAUUUAAAUUGAUUCUCUGUUAUAAGAGUAAACUGAUGAGUUGAAGUCUGGAGAGAAUAACAUUCAUUAUAAAUAAAAUUAUUCUGUGAUCUUUUUUCAAGAUGUGUUAAUAGAAUUUUGUUAUAAAGAGAGAAAUGGAAGUUGGAGUAAGGCUUAACAUGAACUUUAAAACUUGAGUUUUCUCUGAUUUAAAAUUAUUCUUUAGAGCAGGAGCUCCCAACCACCCAGGCCGUGGACUGGUACCAGUCCGUGGCCUGUUAGGAACCAGACCACGCAACAAGAGGUGAGAGGCUGACAAGUGAGCAUUACCAUCUGAGCUCCACUUCCUGUCAGAUCAGCAGCAGCGUUAGAUUCUCAUAGCAGCGGGAACCCUGUUAUGAACCGCAUAUGCAAGGGGUUUGGGUUGUACACUCCUUUUGAGAAUCUAAUGCCUGAUGAUCUGAAGUGGAACAGUUUCAUAGUUUUAUCCUGAAACCAUCCCCUGUCCCAGUCCAUGGAAAAAUUGUCUUCCACGAAACUAGUCCCUACUGCCAAAAGGGUUGGGGACCACUGAUUUAGAGAAGACAUGCUUUAAGUUUUAUGUAGAAUAUAGGCAAGGUAGUAAAAACAGACAUCAUUCUGCAUCAUGUAAGUAUGUGUAGUAAGAAAAAUUUGCUACAGUUUGCCCAAGUAAUCCCAAAGGAAUCAUGAUUGGAUUUUUUUUAAUUGAAGAAAAAGUAAUUGAUGUCUCAAAAUUAUAAUAAAAUAAUUAUAAAAUUAUCCUAGUUUUUUCCAUAAAAGUAAGAUUUAAUUUGGAAGUUUGAGGACAAAAUAGGAUAAAUUUAAGAAACACAAGUAGAGUUAGCAAAUUUGGACAAUAUUUUCCGCCUUAGCACAUUCAGGCUGCUAUAUAAAAUACCAUAAGUGGGUAGCUCAUAAACAAUGGAAAUUUAUUUCCCACAGUUCUGAUGUCUGGAAGUCCAAGAUGGAGGUGCUGGCAGAUUUGGUGAGAGCCUGCUUUCUGGUUCACAGAAGGAGCCUUCUCAUUAUGUCCUUAUAUGAUGAAGGGCCAAACAAGCUCCCUUGGGUGCUAAUCCCAUUUUCAAGGACUCUGCCCUCAUGACCUUAUCACCUCCCAAAAGGCCCCACCACUUAAUACAAUCACUUUGGGAGUUAGGAUUUCAACAAAUGAAUCUCAGGGGGACACAAACAUUCAGACCAUAGGAAUGUUGCAUGCAUAGUUUUGAGUCUAAAUUCAAAGAUUUGGGCACUUAUUUUUAGCAGUGAUUUUUAGAAUUGCUUCUAUUGUAUUUUUUAAAAAUACUGUUAUUCUUCGUUUUCAAUAUAAAUAAUACUGGUUUAAAAAGCUUAGUGCUCUUGGGGACACUGUUUAUAUUUUGUGAGUAUAAUAUACUUGGAAUAGUUAAUCUCAUUCUUAAAAUUCCAUUGUAUUCUGAUGGCUAUUUAAUCUGUUAUGUGCAUAUGCAGGUACAACAGAGCCUGUAUCAUGGAGGGGUCCAGCAUGAGGAAUUCGGACUGGUUUUCAUUUGCCCAUUUGCUGAAAUACAGCCAUUGUUUUUUCCCAAGUGGUAAUCAUUUAAAAUUUUUCCUGGCUUAAGAUAGACGGGAUCUUAAUGCAUACUUCAUUAUGCUGCCUUAAACUUUUAAGAAGAAAAGGAUUUGUACUUGAAAGAAAAACUUGUCAACUUUCUCAAAUCUUUGAUAAAAUAUAAAUUUGACUUAUCAAAGCCUUA